AGGACCGCAGAGCCCCGGAAGCCUAGCCCCAGCCAAGCUGCCCGGGGCGUGACCGGCCUCACGUGACCUGAUGUCACGUGACAGAACCCGCACGUGAUCCGACCUGCGAUGCUGAGGGGAGGAAGCUGCGGAAGUGGACUGGGACUGGAGUUUGGGGUUCUACCCUAGGUUGGGGCGGAGGAAGCUGGAGGAUAGGGGCUGACGCCAGGAACGCUGCAGAGGCGGGUUGGGCGGGGGGCGCUGCCGCCCAAGGCCCGAGGCAGCGGCGCGGGAUCGGCCAAAGCACCGGCCGCCAGUUCGGCGGGUCUGGAGAGAGGGGACCUCAAGCAGCCAGUGGAGCAACCAGCCUGGGAGCCUUCGACGUAGGCGCUGUGGGCGAAGGAAAAGGCCUGGCCUGCUGCCUCUUCUCUUGCAGCAAAAUCCGCUGCUGUGAAGGAGCUGGUAGGCGGACGCUCUGUAGAUAAGAGAAUCCCUGAUCUGCCUGGGCAUCAUCUUGCUCUUUAUGACCUGCUUGGCUGCCACUGUGUAGGGCCUGCUUAAAGUCCUUUGCACUCUCAGCAUUCCCCUCAAGUUCAAGGACAAGCUUCUCAUUAUGGCAGGCAUAAAACUCUUUAUAAUUCGUCCUCCACUCUCCCAGCUCAGGGCUCCAGCUGUUGUCUCACACUUCCUUGAAGUUCCCUCUGCUGAGUCGCCCUUGUGCCUGACCAACUUACUUACUAAAAUAAAAAUCCCAAUUUCUUUCCAGUCAUGUGUGCCCAAGGGCGAGUUAUUUAACUUUUCUGAGCUUUCCUCAGUAAAACGAAGCUACAUAUCUUGCAAGGAUGUGAUAUUAAAGUUAUGAUAUUGUAAAACAGGUGCCACGGUGCUUGGCCUAGGGUGAGCCUUCAACCUAGAACAUACCACUGUCCCCAUGCACCUUGCUCACACACCCAAUCCCAGACUUUUCUUUUGUAGUCACCUCAGUUAUCACCUCAUUAAAUAACCUGAUUACCCCAAGUACAGCUUAAGUGACUUAAGUUAUUUUCUAUGGCUAGCGGAAGGGUCUCCGCUACAUUGGAGAGCUGGGGUGGUCUGGAGUUCCACGGUGUGGUGGGCCAGAGGCCACCUCUCCUGCGGUCUCUUAGUGUCUCGCUGGCGGGGUUCGGCCCGAGCUAGAUAGACACAGCCCUUGGCGGAUUUAAACAACCUAAACAUUAAACAAUACAGCUGCCUCAAAUCUUUGGGAAUUUCAGAAUGACUGACACUGCCAAAGCUGUUCCAAAUUUUGAAGAGAUGUUUGCUAGUAGAUUCACAGAAGAUGACGAGGAGUAUCAGGAAUACUUGAAACGCCCUCCUGAGUCCUCUCCAAUUGUUGAGGAAUGGAAUAGCAGAGCUGGUGGGAACCAAAGAAACAGAGACAAUCGGUUGCAAGAUAGCAGACAGUUCAGAGGCAGGGACGGCAGAUGGGGGUGGCCAAGUGACAAUCGAUCCAAUCAGUGGCGUGGACAAUCCUGCGGUAACAAUUACCCGCAACACAGACAAGAACCUUACUAUCCCGACCAAUAUGGACAUUAAGGUUACAACCAGCUGCCCCCUUACGAUAGAAAUGUUGGCAGCUUUUAGUAAAAGCAUUUACUGUGUUACCACGA